CUUUUGCCCUAGGGAGCGAGUGCGGAGCGAGUGGGAGCGAGACGGCCCUGAGUGGAAGUGUCUGGCUCCCCGUAGAGGCCCUUCUGUACGCCCCGCCGCCCAUGAGCUCGUUCUCACGCGAACAGCGCCGUCGUUAGGCUGGCUCUGUAGCCUCGGCUUACCCCGGGACAGGCCCACGCCUCGCCAGGGAGGGGGCAGCCCGUCGAGGCGCCUCCCUAGUCAGCGUCGGCGUCGCGCUGCGACCCUGGAAGCGGGAGCCGCCGCGAGCGAGAGGAGGAGCUCCAGUGGCGGCGGCGGCGGCGGCAGCGGCAGCGGGCAGCAGCUCCAGCAGCGCCAGCAGGCGGGAUCGAGGCCGUCAACAUGGCGAGCGCCUCGUACCACAUUUCCAAUUUGCUGGAAAAAAUGACAUCCAGCGACAAGGACUUUAGAGAUAGGGUCUCGCUCUGUCACCCACGCUGGAGUGCAGUGGCACCACCUCAACUCACUGCAGCUUCAACCUCCUGGGCUCAAGCGAUUUUCUUCCCACCUCAGCCCCCAGAGUAGCUGGGACUACAGGUUUAUGGCUACAAAUGAUUUGAUGACGGAACUGCAGAAAGAUUCCAUCAAGUUGGAUGAUGAUAGUGAAAGGAAAGUAGUGAAAAUGAUUUUGAAGUUAUUGGAAGAUAAAAAUGGAGAGGUACAGAAUUUAGCUGUCAAAUGUCUUGGUCCUUUAGUGAGUAAAGUGAAAGAAUACCAAGUAGAGACAAUUGUAGAUACCCUCUGCACUAACAUGCUUUCUGAUAAAGAACAACUUCGAGACAUUUCAAGUAUUGGUCUUAAAACAGUAAUUGGAGAACUUCCUCCAGCUUCCAGUGGCUCUGCAUUAGCUGCUAAUGUAUGUAAAAAGAUUACUGGACGUCUUACAAGUGCAAUAGCAAAACAGGAAGAUGUCUCUGUUCAGCUAGAAGCCUUGGAUAUUAUGGCUGAUAUGUUGAGCAGGCAAGGAGGACUUCUUGUUAAUUUCCAUCCUUCAAUUCUGACCUGUCUACUUCCCCAGUUGACCAGCCCUAGACUUGCAGUGAGGAAAAGAACCAUUAUCGCUCUUGGCCAUCUGGUUAUGAGCUGUGGAAAUAUAGUUUUUGUAGAUCUUAUUGAACAUCUGUUGUCAGAGUUGUCCAAAAAUGAUUCUAUGUCAACAACAAGAACCUACAUACAAUGUAUUGCUGCUAUUAGUAGGCAAGCUGGUCAUAGAAUAGGUGAAUACCUUGAGAAGAUAAUUCCUUUGGUGGUAAAAUUUUGCAAUGUAGAUGAUGAUGAAUUAAGAGAGUACUGUAUUCAAGCCUUUGAAUCAUUUGUAAGAAGAUGUCCUAAGGAAGUAUAUCCUCAUGUUUCUACCAUUAUAAAUAUUUGUCUUAAAUAUCUUACCUAUGAUCCAAAUUAUAAUUACGAUGAUGAAGAUGAAGAUGAAAAUGCAAUGGAUGCUGAUGGUGGUGAUGAUGAUGAUCAAGGGAGUGAUGAUGAAUACAGUGAUGAUGAUGACAUGAGUUGGAAAGUGAGACGUGCAGCUGCGAAGUGCUUGGAUGCUGUAGUUAGCACAAGGCAUGAAAUGCUUCCAGAAUUCUACAAGACCGUCUCUCCUGCACUAAUAUCCAGAUUUAAAGAGCGUGAAGAGAAUGUAAAGGCAGAUGUUUUUCACGCAUACCUUUCUCUUUUGAAGCAAACUCGUCCUGUACAAAGUUGGCUAUGUGACCCUGAUGCAAUGGAGCAGGGAGAAACACCUUUAACAAUGCUUCAGAGUCAGGUUCCCAACAUUGUUAAAGCUCUUCACAAACAGAUGAAAGAAAAAAGUGUGAAGACCCGACAGUGUUGUUUUAACAUGUUAACUGAGCUGGUAAAUGUAUUACCUGGGGCCCUAACUCAACACAUUCCUGUACUUGUACCAGGAAUCAUUUUCUCACUGAAUGAUAAAUCAAGCUCAUCGAAUUUGAAGAUCGAUGCUUUGUCAUGUCUAUACGUAAUCCUCUGUAACCAUUCUCCUCAAGUCUUCCAUCCUCACGUUCAGGCUUUGGUUCCUCCAGUGGUGGCUUGUGUUGGAGACCCAUUUUACAAAAUUACAUCUGAAGCACUUCUUGUUACUCAACAGCUUGUCAAAGUAAUUCGUCCUUUAGAUCAGCCUUCCUCGUUUGAUGCAACUCCUUAUAUCAAAGAUCUAUUUACCUGUACCAUUAAGAGAUUAAAAGCAGCUGACAUUGAUCAGGAAGUCAAGGAAAGGGCUAUUUCCUGUAUGGGACAAAUUAUUUGCAACCUUGGAGACAAUUUGGGUUCUGACUUGCCUAAUACACUUCAGAUUUUCUUGGAGAGACUAAAGAAUGAAAUUACCAGGUUAACUACAGUAAAGGCAUUGACACUGAUUGCUGGGUCACCUUUGAAGAUAGAUUUGAGGCCUGUUCUGGGAGAAGGGGUUCCUAUCCUUGCUUCAUUUCUUAGAAAAAACCAGAGAGCUUUGAAACUGGGUACUCUUUCUGCCCUUGAUAUUCUAAUAAAAAACUAUAGUGACAGCUUGACAGCUGCCAUGAUUGAUGCAGUUCUAGAUGAGCUCCCACCUCUUAUCAGCGAAAGUGAUAUGCAUGUUUCACAAAUGGCCAUCAGUUUUCUUACCACUUUGGCAAAAGUAUAUCCCUCCUCCCUUUCAAAGAUAAGUGGAUCCAUUCUCAAUGAACUUAUUGGACUUGUGAGAUCACCCUUAUUGCAGGGGGGAGCUCUUAGUGCCAUGCUAGACUUUUUCCAAGCUCUGGUUGUCACUGGAACAAAUAAUUUAGGAUACAUGGAUUUGUUGCGCAUGCUGACUGGUCCAGUUUACUCUCAGAGCACAGCUCUUACUCAUAAGCAGUCUUAUUAUUCCAUUGCCAAAUGUGUAGCUGCCCUUACUCGAGCAUGCCCUAAAGAGGGACCAGCUGUAGUAGGUCAGUUUAUUCAAGAUGUCAAGAACUCAAGGUCUACAGAUUCCAUUCGUCUCUUAGCUCUACUUUCUCUUGGAGAAGUUGGGCAUCAUAUUGACUUAAGUGGACAGUUGGAACUAAAAUCUGUAAUACUAGAAGCUUUCUCAUCUCCUAGUGAAGAAGUCAAAUCAGCUGCAUCCUAUGCAUUAGGCAGCAUUAGUGUGGGCAACCUUCCUGAAUAUCUGCCGUUUGUCCUGCAAGAAAUAACUAGUCAACCCAAAAGGCAGUAUCUUUUACUUCAUUCCUUGAAGGAAAUUAUUAGCUCUGCAUCAGUGGUGGGCCUUAAACCAUAUGUUGAAAACAUCUGGGCCUUAUUACUAAAGCACUGUGAGUGUGCAGAGGAAGGAACCAGAAAUGUUGUUGCUGAAUGUCUAGGAAAACUCACUCUAAUUGAUCCAGAAACUCUCCUUCCACGGCUUAAGGGGUACUUGAUAUCAGGCUCAUCAUAUGCCCGAAGCUCAGUGGUUACGGCUGUGAAAUUUACAAUUUCUGACCAUCCACAACCUAUUGAUCCACUGUUAAAGAACUGCAUAGGUGAUUUCCUAAAAACUUUGGAAGACCCAGAUUUGAAUGUGAGAAGAGUAGCCUUGGUCACAUUUAAUUCAGCAGCACAUAACAAGCCAUCAUUAAUAAGGGAUCUAUUGGAUACUGUUCUUCCACAUCUUUACAAUGAAACAAAAGUUAGAAAGGAGCUUAUAAGAGAGGUAGAAAUGGGUCCAUUUAAACAUACGGUUGAUGAUGGUCUGGAUAUUAGAAAGGCAGCAUUUGAGUGUAUGUACACACUUCUAGACAGUUGUCUUGAUAGACUUGAUAUCUUUGAAUUUCUAAAUCAUGUUGAAGAUGGUUUGAAGGACCAUUAUGAUAUUAAGAUGCUGACAUUUUUAAUGUUGGUGAGACUGUCUACCCUUUGUCCAAGUGCAGUACUGCAGAGGUUGGACCGACUUGUUGAGCCAUUACGUGCAACAUGUACAACUAAGGUAAAGGCAAACUCAGUAAAGCAGGAGUUUGAAAAACAAGAUGAAUUAAAGCGAUCUGCCAUGAGAGCAGUAGCAGCACUGCUAACCAUUCCAGAAGCAGAGAAGAGUCCACUGAUGAGUGAAUUCCAGUCACAGAUCAGUUCUAACCCUGAGCUGGCGGCUAUCUUUGAAAGUAUCCAGAAAGAUUCAUCAUCUACUAACUUGGAAUCAAUGGACACUAGUUAGAUGUUUGUUCACCAUGGGGACCAUUACAUAUGACCAUACAAUGCACUGAAUUGACAGGUUAAUCAUAAGACAUGGAAAGAGAAGUGUCUAAAAGCUUCAAAAUGUUCCACUUUUUUUUCCUUCAUGGAGACUGUUUGUUUGGCUUUCUUCCAUUGUUGUUUUUGUAGCAUUUAUUUCAGAAAUGUGUAUUUCCAUAAUCCAGAGGUUGUAAAACCACUAGUGUUUUAGUGGUUACAGCAACAUUUGAAAUGGAAACUAAAAGUUAGGAUUUUAUGGAGUAUGGAGAUAGGGUCCAGUAUCUAUUUACCCUGUAAUGUUUAGGAUUAAAAUGUUAAAAUUUUGUGACCAUGAAUUUCUUUCUUUUAUAAAUUUUCUCAUUUAAAAAUCAAAAAUCUUGCAAAACAAAAACCAUGUUUCUUUUUCUUGUAUAACUUUUUGUUUUCAGCAACAUAAAUUGAUUUUUAGCUGGCAGACAAGAAUAUCCAUAUAAGAUUUGUUAACCAUUUCAGAGAGUUUGGCAAUUUUUAAAAGAUAAUAAGGUAUCAUUUUUAAGUAUGAAAAUUAACAAUAUCCCUGUUGCGCACACUAAUUUUGCAUGAGUAAGUUUACAAAUAUGUAUCGUCUGUAAAGCAGCAUGUGCAGAUUAUUCAUAAUAUAGAAGUUAAAAUAAGUAUUAGUGCAAUUUUCAGAUAUUUAUUUUUGCACAGAAAACACAUUAUCUGGAGAGAAAGAAAGGAGAAUUUUUGAGACUUGGGUUUUCUUAAUGCCAGUGUGAAUUUGCAGAUGUUUUCAGAAAAUCAAGUCACAGUAACAAUUUGCCACUUUUUUCUAUUAUAAAUCUUCUUACUUAAAUUUUGAAUAUUUAGUUUUUCUCAGUUACCCAUUUGUGUGUGUGUGAUUCCACUUAGAAAUUCUUAAAACCAGAUUUUUCUUUCAUUCCGUUUGGAUGUCUACAUUCCUUAUCAAAGGAUAUAAAUACUGUGUAUGCUUUUGAAUUUUAUUUUUAGGAAAAUUCUGAAGCCAGCUAUCACAGGUUUGUUAGCUAAUAAUAGUAUUUUCUUUUAGUUGAGUUAGGUUUUUCCCCAUCUCCUGUAGAGCGAAUUUACAUAUUGUAUUGGGUAAGUGUUCACUACUUUUCCUGAUUAAGGGAUCUGUGCUGGGGAACAAAGCUUUUGCAGUACCUUAUAUUGUAGUUAAAAUUUUAUUUAACAUAUCCUUCAGUGAGCUCAUUUCACACUGUAGCCUCUUCCUUAAAAUUUGUGGUGCUCCUGUAACAGUAAGAACUAAUUCUGAAAUAAAAGACAUCUCCUAAUGCUGUGCAAACAUAGUUUACAUGUAUUGAAGGAGGCAGUUGUUAAAUUGAGUGACCAAUUUAAGCAAUCAGAUAUUUGAAAACUGCACCCUUUAGUUUUGAAACUGUGAAUUAGAAACACUUUUCCUGCUGUAUUACUACCUGCUUUAACAUCCAAAUAUACAGUGAUUUUAAAUGAUAACAUACUGUGGUUAUUAGAUUAACAGCUUGAUUUUGAAUGUUCAGAUGAUAAUGCAGAAGACAUCACUUCUAGUAAGGAUUUUGACUAGUGCAUUGAUGUUGAAGUUGGUGCCAUUUCAAAAUGUGGCAGGUGAUAAUCUUUUACCAUAAUUUGCAUAAAACUGUAAUAGAAGUUUAUUUUGAGAUGUUAGUAUAUUAUGUACUAUGCAUUUCUGUGGUAUAGAUGUUGUGGAUAUAUUUAAGUAUUUGGUUACAUGGUUUUACAAUAAAUUACAAUACUGCAGGCUCUAGGACUGAACAGGAGACUGACAUGCAUAUGUUGUGUGAAUGUCUUAGUUGGGUAAAGUUAAAUCCAAAUACUUCAACUGGCUUUUUCUUCAGUUUGUUUGUUUUUAACUUUCAAGAUGCAUGUUUUGUUUUGUUUUGCUUUGUUUUUGUCUCUUAAGCCAAUUCAUUUUUCUAACAGUUGAAAUUCUUUUAGUACUAAAGAAAUAGAUACUGCUCUUUUAUGGCUUUAGUGUUUAUAUACCUGUUUAUAUGCAUACAUUAACAAAAUUAGUAACAGCAGUGCUUAGAAUUUCAAUGCUGUGUCAUACUGAUGAUUAACUCCAUACUCCUAGUGGUGAUGUGGUCCAGAUACUGGAAUGGAAGUGGCAGGAUGUGGAGUCCAGACAUAGUCUACCACUCAUGCUACUUACUAGUAAUAUUAAGGUGUUAAACUUAGGAAUUUGUCACAUGUAGGUUCCUGAGGAGAUCUAAAAGUUAAUACAAAACCAAGCUGUUUACUGAUUUUCAUGAGAACAUUUAAGUUAGUUUAGGUCUACCUGAUUUAUUUUAAAAGAAGGCAGAGGGCUGGACGCAGUGGCUUACGCCUGUAAUCCCAGCACUUUGGGAGGCCGAGGCGGGCGGAUCACGAGGUCAGGAGAUCGAGACUAUCCUGGCUAACACUGUGAAAACCCAUCUCUACUGAAAAUACAAAAAAUUAGCUGGGCGUGGUGGCAGACGCCUGUAGUCCUAGCUGCUACAGCUGAGGCAGGAGAAUGGCGUGAACCCAGGAGGCGGAGCUGGCAGUGAGCCGAGAUCACGCCACUGCACUCUGGCCUGGGCAACAGAGCGAGAGUCUGUCUCAAAAAAAAAAAAAAAAAAAAGGCAGGAAGGAAAUUUGGUAUGGCAGGGCCUAACCUAAAAGGUUAUUUAUAAAAUCAAUAGCACUGAAUGAUAAUUUUUUUAAUGACAGUCAUGUAUUUUAUUAAUGAUAUCUGAAAGCUGCUUAACCAUUAGGAAUUACAAUUCUUUAUGGUUGGAGUAUGAUGAUUUCAUCAAAUGUUUGAAUAUUUACAUAAUUUUUAUGUAACCAUAAUUAAACCAAAUUAGUCUUUUUUUCUUCAUACUUUUCUUCGGUAAAUAGUGAAGAAAUAAUGGGCAUAUCUAAUUAACCAGUUCUAGUGGGUGUUGUGAUAUCUUUAUAUCUAGUUCAGUCUCAGAUGUAUGAAUAUGAUUAUAUAGUCAUGAUUGAAGUUCAAAAUGAGGAAGUAUACAAAAUCCUCAGCCACUGAAAAAUUCAGUUAACUUGUUUAUACUCCUGUAAGCUCUAGUUAGUCACAAGACAAAGUAUAUAGUAACACUUUGUAAUGAAGUAACAUUUUCUGCCCACAUUAAUUUUACUAAAGACCUAAAUUGUUAAAAUUAAUUGCCAAUCUCUGGAUAUAUUAUGCUUAGUAAGUGUUUUGAAAUUAAAGACCUUAAACAUUUCAGCAAGUAAAUUUUGGAUUCUAGCUCUGUUUUAAAUUGAAUCCUAAUUUUCAAACCACUGCUACCCCAGAUUCAUACCUGUUUUUGAAAUCUUGUUUAUGGAAUGGAAAAUUGACAGUAUGGUAAUAGUUUAUUGACUGAUUGGACAAAGGAUAUUCUGGUUUUAACUGACUUUUCCAUUUAAAUAAAAUUCAUUUGAUAAUUUUGGUUGCAAAAGUGGAACACAGUGGAAGUAUUUGGCUACAGGCUACCCAAAUCUCAUCAGAUAAGGCUGUUUUCUUAAAGGAAAUGCAAAAUGAAAUCAUAUGUUUUCCUUUUCCAAUACAGUAAAUUGCUUGUUUUCCUAUGAAUAUCAGAAAAGAUUUUGUAAACACCUUUGCUGUAGUUUCAGGCAAGAUCUUUCAGCAACAUGUUUUUGCUCUUUGUAACUUAGAAAGUUAGCUCUGAAUCCAAAAACUACUGAAGUGAGUAAUGCAUAUAAUUUUACUUUUUUGGACCCUAUAAUGCCAGUGUGUCAGGUUUCAGAAUGAUAUUUAGUAGACAGAAAUACCUAAUUUUGUUUUGGAAUCUUAAUACCCUGUCCUCUUCAUAACUUUCUAGUGGUGAUUUUAGCAAGUUUAAUUAUUUUGCUGAGGUCUUAGAAGACAGAAAGCUUAUGCUAUGUAAAGUGACAUUGUUUCCAGAUUAGGAAGUAUUGGAAUUAAUUUGCUAUUGCCAGUAAGUAAUGGUUGAUGGAUAUUAAGUGAUUUUAGUCUAGAAUGCUCUCAAAAAAAUAGUAAAGAAUUGUACUUCAGGGCCAGAUGGCAGCUCACGCCUGUAAUCUCAGCACUUUGGGAGGCCAAGGUGGGGGAUCACUUGAAGACAGGAGUUGGAGACCAGCUCUAGGCAACAUAGUGAGACCCUGUCUCUACCAAAAAGAAGAAAAAAGAAAUCAACAACAUGCAACCAUAAGAAUGGAUGAGAUGGCCCUAAAAGAAUAAGGAUUACAUAUAAUGAGAAGACGUGUGGGCUGAAAUACCUAGUGAACAAUAUUUAAGGGAAACUGAAGUGCAAAUGGCCUCACAGGUUUGUUUUUGUGUUUAAGACAAGGUCUCACUCUGUUGCCUGGACUGGAGUACAUAGCACGAACAUGGUUUACUGCACCUCAGCUUCCUGGGCACAAGUGAUUCUCCCACCUCAGCCUCCCGAGUAGCUGGGAGUAUAGGUGUGUGCCACCACGUCCAGCUAAUUUUUUUAUUUCCUUGUGGAGAUGGGGUCUCAUGACCUUGUCCAGGAUGAUCUCAAACUCCUGGGCUCAAGCAAUCCUGUGUUGGCCUCCUAAACUGCUGAGAUUAUUGCAAGUGCCUCCUUGCCCAGCCACAUGUUGUUGAUUUCUUUUUUCUUUUUUUUUCUUUCUUAAUUUUUUUUUUUUUUUUUUUUUUUGAGAUUGAUGGAGUCUUGCUUUGUCUCCCAGGCUGGAGUGCAGUGGCGCAAUAUCGGCUCACUGCAACCUCUGCCUCCCGGGUUCUAGCUAUUCUCCUGCCUCAGCCUCCCAAGUAGCUGUGAUUACAGGCGUGUGCCACCAUGCCCAGCUAAUUUUUGUAUUUUUAGUAGAGAUGGAGUUUUGCCAUGUUGGCCAGGCUGGUUUCAAACUCCUGAUCUUAGGUGAUACACCCGCCUCGGCCUCCCAAAGUGCUGGGAUUACAGGCGUGAGCCACGUCCCCCAGCCAGUUUCUUAAUCUAUACAUCUAGCCCAGUCCAUGCCCCUGUUUCAGACUAUUAUAUCCAACCACCUGCUAUACAUCUCAUAAAGGUAUCUCAAACACAGCAUAUCUAAAGCUGAAGUCAUCAUCUUGCCCUGGUUUUUCCUGUCUCUUUGCUGAUGGCAUCCCAUUUACCCAGUCAUUCAAACUGGAAAUCUAAAAGCCUCACUUAGCAAGAGUUUGGAGGCAGAAUAUGAUAAAGAACAAGGACUCUGGGAGGCCAAGGCAGGUGGAUUGCUUGAGGUCAAGAGUUCGAGACCAGUCUGGCCAACAUGGCGAAACCCCGUCUUUGCUAAAAAAACACAAAGAAAUUAGCUAGACGUGGUGGCACAUGCCUGUAGUCCCAGCUGUGUGGGAGGCUGAGGCAGGGGAAUUGCUUGAACCUGGGAGGUGGAGGUUGCAGUGACCCAAGAUUGCAUGCACCACUGCACUCCAGCCUGGGUGACAAAGCGAGACCCUGUCUCAAAAAAAACAAGGACUCUACAGAUAGAUAGACAUCAUAUAUCAUAUUAGUUUGAAUCCUGGCUGUUAGCUGUUAGACUUGGGCAAAUAAUUUAACCUCAACUUUCCCUAUCUAUAAAAUGGGAAUUAAAAUAUUUGCACCUUAUAGGGUUAUUGUGAGGAUUAAAUAGGAACAUUGUAUAAAGCACUUAAAACAGUACCUGGGACAUACUAAGUAAUAUAAUUGUUAACUCUUACUAGCAUUCUGUCCCUUUUAUUUCCUAAAUAUCUCUCAUGCCCAUCUCCUAAAUAUCUCUUUCCUAAAUAUCUCUCAUGCUUUUGGCUUAAGACCUCUUUUCCUCCUUAUCUAUUGACUGGACUGCGGCAAAUGCCUGCUAAUCGUUAUUUUUGUGUUCAUUCAUUUAGCAAGCCAAUUUAUUACGCGCUUAGGGUGCUGCCAGGGCUACAAAAGCUGUUGAGACUGUACUUGAUAUGAAGAAGCUUGCUGAUUAUCAUGGGAAGACUGACAUAAGGAAGCACCAUAAAAUUCUGCUGUAUGAGAGGUAUACACGGGAUACUGGGGGUUAAUAAUUGAGGGUAUGGUCCAUUCAACAUGAGUGAGACAGAAACAAUUCAUAAAGGAGAUGAAAUGUCUUGAGGAAUGAGCUCUUAGAAGAAUAGUUUUCAAAUGAGUGUGCAUCACAGUCACCUGUAAGACUUAUUAAAACAGAUCGCUGGGCCCUACACCCAGAGGCUGUGGUUCAGUAGGCUGUAGUAAACCAGUAAUUUGUAUUUCUAUGACGUUCCCAGGUUCUAAUGCUGUUCCCCAAGGCCACACCUUGGAAACCACCACAUUAAAAUACCCAGAAGGCAUUAAUUCCCAGUCCUUCCUCUACACAGCUGCAAAACAAUGGUCCUGACCAUUUCAUCUUUGCACUACAUCCUUCACUGUCUCUCUUUUGCCCAUAGGAUAAGUACAAACUAGAUCUGGUUACUGCCUGCCCCACCAGCCUCAGCAUCUCUCACAACUAGGACUAACUUUUUCUUCUGACAACUAUAAAAUAUUUCCCUUGCCUUCUCAAGUUUGCUCAAGGUCAAGUUAUGCCUUUUGCCUGGAAUGACUUGACUUCUCUUUUGUUUUACUUAGCUGGCUGCUUUUCAUCUUGUAGGUUAGGUCAAGGACUCCAGGAAGUCUUCCCUGGACAAGUAAUGAAGAGGGCAUAAUCCAAGGGCCAACUCCCAUGUUUGGAACCUGACUCCAUUUUCAGGCACGUAAUAUUGUCAAAUUCCUUUUAAAAGCACCUGUCUGUCUGUUAACGUUGGUGCAGAUACUGCUAUUCCCCUCCUCCAUACCAUUGCUGAUGGUUACUGAGGGUAUGGGAAGGGCCGACUAGUCCAGCUGUUCACAAACAGCCCUUAAUGUCAAACUGAAUACUGCCAACGUAGUUCCAGUUUCUGUAUCUAAAGACUCAGCUUGGAGUCACUUGUCUGGACUAAAAGUAACCCCUCCUUGUCUGGUUUGUGACUUUCUGUACUCUGAUGCCCCCAGCUUUCUGCCUUCUAGAAAUUUGUCAGAAUUUCCAAAAUUCUUGGGCCUUCCUUCUUGCUCUAUAUAUGGUUUUGGAUUCAUUCCUUUUAAAAAAUAUUUACUGUCAUUUCAGUAGAAUUUUGACACAAUAAAUAUAAGCACAUCAGA